AGACACGGACUUGGGAAUGUUUUGAAACAACAGGAACGACAUCACCCUAGGUUUGUGUUUUCAAGCCAGAUAUUCCGGCGUGGAUGCUAAGAAUUCUUACAUGGGCAAGUAUUAAUAUUUGAAUGCAGCCGUGAUUGAGGUGGAGGUGGAGACAAAAGGCGUGCGUCCCUAGAACAUGUUUUGUCCCCACUGCCGGAGGGAAUAUUCUGUGUCAGCUAUCGCACGCACCCUUUCCCUCCAUGUGAGUGGACUCCACACUCUAAGCAAGGCGCUCUGGACUGCAAACUCAGCUUGUGCCUCUCUCCAGCCCUGUGGCCUCGCUGGACAAUUUUUCUAAUCUCUUUGGAGCUGAUCUUCAUGUUGAAAAAGGACAAGUCCCAUCUUCAGAUCAACACCUGUCCCAGCGCUGCCAUUUUGCCAAGGCUCCUCCUUGGAGUGUUUGUAAGGCACUUUUGCCACGAAGUAACCCAGCCACCAGCCUCAGUGGAACCUCCAAGCCUAAUUCUGGAGGAGACUUUAACUCGGUGACCAAAAGCCAGCCCCACUGUGAGUUGAACUCUUUCGUGUUGACCGGCCACUCUCCGUGCUCUGGAUGAUGUCGGAACACGACCUGGCCGAUGUGGUUCAGAUUGCAGUGGAAGACCUGAGCCCUGACCACCCAGGUACAGAGCUGUGGGACAGUAGUUGUUUUGGAGAAUCAUGUAGUGACAGAUGAAGACGAACCUGCUUUGAAACGCCAGCGACUAGAAAUCAAUUGCCAGGAUCCAUCUAUAAAGUCAUUCCUGUAUUCCAUCAACCAGACAAUCUGCUUGCGGUUGGAUAGCAUUGAAGCCAAAUUGCAAGCCCUGGAGGCUACUUGUAAAUCCUUAGAAGAAAAGCUGGAUCUGGUCACGAACAAGCAGCACAGCCCCAUCCAGGUCCCCAUGGUGGCCGGCUCCCCUCUCGGGGCAACCCAGACGUGCAACAAAGUGCGAUGCGUCGUCCCCCAGACUACAGUAAUACUCAACAAUGAUCGGCAGAACGCCAUUGUAGCCAAGAUGGAAGACCCCUUGAGCAACAGGGCACCGGAUUCCCUGGAAAAUGUCAUUAGCAACGCUGUGCCUGGGCGUCGGCAGAACACCAUUGUGGUGAAGGUGCCGGGCCAAGAAGACAGCCACCACGAGGACGGGGAGAGCGGCUCGGAGGCCAGCGACUCUGUGUCCAGCUGUGGGCAGGCGGGCAGUCAGAGCAUCGGGAGCAACGUCACGCUCAUCACCCUGAACUCGGAAGAGGACUACCCCAAUGGCACCUGGCUGGGCGACGAGAACAACCCCGAGAUGCGGGUACGCUGCGCCAUCAUCCCCUCCGACAUGCUGCACAUCAGCACCAACUGCCGCACGGCCGAGAAGAUGGCGCUCACGCUGCUGGACUACCUCUUCCACCGCGAGGUGCAGGCUGUGUCCAACCUCUCGGGGCAGGGCAAGCACGGGAAGAAGCAGCUGGACCCGCUCACCAUCUACGGCAUCCGGUGUCACCUUUUCUAUAAAUUUGGCAUCACAGAAUCCGACUGGUACCGAAUCAAGCAGAGCAUCGACUCCAAGUGCCGCACGGCGUGGCGGCGCAAGCAGCGGGGCCAGAGCCUGGCGGUCAAGAGCUUCUCGCGGAGAACGCCCAACUCGUCCUCCUACUGCCCUUCAGAGCCGAUGAUGAGCACCCCACCUCCUGCCAGCGAGCUCCCGCAGCCACAGCCGCAGCCGCAGGCCCUGCACUACGCGCUGGCCAACGCACAGCAGGUGCAGAUCCACCAGAUCGGAGAAGACGGACAGGUGCAAGUAGGACACCUCCACAUCGCCCAGGUGCCGCAGGGGGAGCAAGUCCAGAUCACGCAGGACAGCGAGGGCAACCUCCAGAUCCAUCACGUGGGGCAGGACGGUCAGGUGCUGCAGGGUGCACAGCUGAUCGCCGUGGCCUCCUCGGACCCCGCGGCGGCGGGCGUGGAUGGGUCGCCACUCCAGGGCAGCGACAUCCAGGUUCAGUACGUGCAGCUGGCGCCAGUGAGUGACCACACGGCCGGGGCACAGACGGCCGAAGCCCUGCAGCCCACGCUACAGCCGGAGAUGCAGCUCGAGCACGGGGCCAUCCAGAUUCAGUGAGCGGUGCCCAUGGCACCAGGAGCCCCUCGCCGGCUCCGCCUACGGCCCGGCCCCCACGCGCCCUGCUCUCACGGCCUCGGCACAGGCAGCGGCUGCACGUGUUCUGCUGAAGUGCGUCUGAAGGCCGCUGCCUCCGCGGGGAACAGCAUCCUAUCAACUGAAAGAGCAGCCGCCGCCGCCCCCAGCCGGAGACCCCUUUCGUUUGAGUCCUGCUGUUGGUGUCGGAGCACGAGGGGAGGCACGGUGCGGAGAGCGUCGCAUAUGCGCGGGAAAUCAAGAACUAUGAUAUUUUUCUGUUUAAACAGCUUUUUUUAAUUUGCUAUGGUGUUUAUAACAAAAAAGAAAAUUUGAAAAAAAAAAUCCCAGGGGAGUAGCAGGAGCCCUUUGCUGUGUGCUCUGUCCAGUGUCAUGAGACGGGAGCCCUUUGCUGUGUGCUCUGUCCAGUGUCAUGAGACGGGAGCCCUUUGCUGUGUGCUCUGUCCAGUGUCAUGAGACGGGAGCCCUUUGCUGUGUGCUCUGUCCAGUGUCAUGAGGCAGGUGUUUGCAAAGCCAGCUCUCGGUUCCGAUGGGGUAUUGCUGACCUACUUUUCUAGGGGAAAUGCUCUUAAACACUGUAAUUAUGCAUUUCUAAUGAAAUAAAAUGUAUUUAUGACCA